CGCUCUGUCACCCAGGCAGGAGUGCAGCGGCACGAUCUCAGCUCACUGCAGCCUUCACCUCCCGGGUUCAAGCGCUCCUCCUGCCUCAGCCUCCUGAGUAGCUGGGAUUACAGGCAUGUGCCAUCACACCCAGCUAAUUUUUGUAUUUUUAGUAGAGACGGGGUUUCACCACGUUGGCCAGGCUGGUCUCAAAUUCCUGACCUCGUGAUCCACCCGCCUCGGCCUCCCGAACUGUUGGGAUUACAGGCGUGAGCCACCGUGCCUGGCCAGAACUGCACACUUAAACGUGUUCGAGAUGGUAAACUUUAGGCUAACCUUGCCGCGGGCCGAGCCCUGCCUCGCCAUGGACCAGGACUAUGAGCGGCGCCUGCUUCGCCAGAUCGUCAUCCAGAAUGAGAACACGAUGCCACGCGUCACAGAGAUGCGGCGGACCCUGACGCCUGCCAGCUCCCCAGUGUCCUCGCCCAGCAAGCACGGAGACCGCUUCAUCCCCUCCAGAGCCGGAGCCAACUGGAGCGUGAACUUCCACAGGAUUAACGAGAAUGAGAAGUCUCCCAGUCAGAACCGGAAAGCCAAGGACGCCACCUCAGACAACGGCAAAGACGGCCUGGCCUACUCUGCCCUGCUCAAGAAUGAGCUGCUGGGUGCCGGCAUCGAGAAGGUGCAGGACCCGCAGACUGAGGACCGCAGGCUGCAGCCCUCCACGCCUGAGAAGAAGGGUCUGUUCACGUAUUCCCUUAGCACCAAGCGCUCCAGCCCCGAUGACGGCAACGAUGUGUCUCCCUACUCCCUGUCUCCCGUCAGCAACAAGAGCCAGAAGCUGCUCCGGUCCCCCCGGAAACCCACCCGCAAGAUCUCCAAGAUCCCCUUCAAGGUGCUGGACGCGCCCGAGCUGCAGGACGACUUCUACCUCAAUCUGGUGGACUGGUCGUCCCUCAAUGUGCUCAGCGUGGGGCUAGGCACCUGCGUGUACCUGUGGAGUGCCUGUACCAGCCAGGUGACGCGGCUCUGUGACCUCUCAGUGGAAGGGGACUCAGUGACCUCCGUGGGCUGGUCUGAGCGGGGGAACCUGGUGGCGGUGGGCACACACAAGGGCUUCGUGCAGAUCUGGGACGCAGCCGCAGGGAAGAAGCUGUCCAUGUUGGAGGGCCACACGGCACGCGUCGGGGCGCUGGCCUGGAAUGCUGAGCAGCUGUCGUCCGGGAGCCGCGACCGCAUGAUCCUGCAGAGGGACAUCCGCACCCCGCCACUGCAGUCGGAGCGGCGGCUGCAGGGCCACCGGCAGGAGGUGUGCGGGCUCAAGUGGUCCACAGACCACCAGCUCCUCGCCUCGGGGGGCAACGACAACAAGCUGCUGGUCUGGAAUCACUCGAGCCUGAGCCCCGUGCAGCAGUACACGGAGCACCUGGCGGCCGUGAAGGCCAUCGCCUGGUCCCCACAUCAGCACGGGCUGCUGGCCUCGGGGGGCGGCACAGCUGACCGCUGUAUCCGCUUCUGGAACACGCUGACAGGACAACCACUGCAGUGUAUCGACACGGGCUCCCAAGUGUGCAAUCUGGCCUGGUCCAAGCACGCCAACGAGCUGGUGAGCACGCACGGCUACUCACAGAACCAGAUCCUUGUCUGGAAGUACCCCUCCCUGACCCAGGUGGCCAAGCUGACCGGGCACUCCUACCGCGUGCUGUACCUGGCAAUGUCCCCUGAUGGGGAGGCCAUCGUCACUGGUGCUGGAGACGAGACCCUGAGGUUCUGGAACGUCUUUAGCAAAACCCGUUCGACAAAGGUAAAGUGGGAGUCUGUGUCUGUGCUCAACCUCUUCACCAGGAUCCGGUAAACCUGCCGGGCAGGACCGUGCCACACCAGCUGUCCAGAGUCGGAGGACCCCAGCUCCUCAGCUUGCAUGGACUCUGCCUUCCCAGCGCUUGUCCCCCGAGGAAGGCGGCUGGGCGGGCGGGGAGCUGGGCCUGGAGGAUCCUGGAGUCUCAUUAAAUGCCUGAUUGUGAACCAUGUCCACCAGUAUCUGGGGUGGGCACGUGGUCGGGGACCCUCAGCAGCAGGGGCUCUGUCUCCCUUCCCAAAGGGCGAGAACCACAUUGGACGGUCCCGGCUCAGACCGUCUGUACUCAGAGCGACGGAUGCCCCCUGGGACCCUCACUGCCUCCGUCUGUUCAUCACCUGCCCACCGGAGCCGCAUGCUCUUCCUGGAACUGCCCACGUCUGCACAGAACAGACCACCAGACGCCAGGGCUGAUUGGUGGGGGCCUGAGACCCCGGUUGCCCAUUCAUGGCUGCACCCCACCAUGUCAAACCCAAGACCAGCCCCAAGGCCAGACCAAGGCAUGUAGGCCUGGGCAGGUGGCUCGGGGCCACUGGCGGAGCCAGCCUGUGGAUCCAAGAGACAGUCCCCACCUGGGCUUCACGGCAUCCUUGCAGCCACCUCUGCUGUCACUGCUCGAAGCAGCAGUCUCUCUGGAAGCAUCUGUGUCAUGGCCAUCGCCCGGCGGUCAGUGGGCUUCAGAUGGGCCUGUGCAUCCUGGCCAAGCGUCACCCUCACACUGGAGGAGGAUGUCUGCUCUGGACUUAUCACCCCAGGAGAACUGAACCCGGACCUGCUCACUGCCCUGGCUGGAGAGGAGCACAACAGAUGCCACGUCUUCGUGCAUUCGCCAACACGUGCCCUCACAGGGCCAGCGUCCUCCUUCCCUGCGCAAGACUUGCGUCCCCCAUGCCUGCUGGGUGGCUGGGUCCUGUGGAGGCCAGCAGCGGUGUGGCCCCCGCCCCCAGGCUGCCUGUGUCUUCACCUGUCCUGUCCACCAGCGCCAACAGCCGUGGGGAAGCCAAGGAGACCCAAGGGGUCCAGGAGGUGGGCGCCCUCCAUCCUUCGAGAAGCUUCCCAGGCUCCUCUGCUUCUCUGUCUCAUGCUCCCAGGCUGCACAGCAGGCAGGGAGGGAGGCAAGGCAGGGGAGUGGGGCCUGAGCUGAGCACUGCCCCCUCACCCCCCCACCACCCCUUCCCAUUUCAUCGGUGGGGACGUGGAGAGGGUGGGGCGGGCUGGGGUUGGAGGGUCCCACCCACCACCCUGCUGUGCUUGGGAACCCCCACUCCCCACUCCCCACAUCCCAACAUCCUGGUGUCUGUCCCCAGUGGGGUUGGCGUGCAUGUGUACAUAUGUAUUUGUGACUUUUCUUUGGAUUUGUUUUGUGUUUUUGUUGACUAGUCCUGGAAAUGUUUGAGGCUAGACGGGGAGGGGCCAGGACCCACCCACUGCUCCUGGGGGAUGAGGUCCUGGUUUUAAAGCCCCGUCAUUUCAAGCGGGUCGAUCUUCCACAUUCACUGGAGAGACUCUCCCCACCUCUGUCUGGGUGGGGCGCGGACCCCUCACUGUGCGCCUGUGCAGGGGGUGCUGGUGCACGUGGCAGUGUGGAUUUCCAGUGGUCACGGUCUUACUGUUUCAAGGUUUUUAAAUAAGAAAACCAACCCUGCCUUCGCCCAUGCCCGCCCCUGCCCGCAGUUGCCAAAGAGCCGCCUUGUCGCUGUGGGCGUCAGGGCUUGGCUGGCUCAGUGCACAACCCACAGUGGCCUUCAGAGGCUCCUCCUGGGACUGGGAACCGCCGCAGGGCCAGGCGGACGGCGUGAGGUUUGUGUUGGGGCUGGUUCUGCCCAUGCUAGGGGGUGGGGGAGCUCCCAGGACAGACCAGCCUUGUUUCUCAUGUAAUGCAGUGACGCUGUCAUUAAACACGUGGAUUCAUGUGUGGCCGGGACUGGCUGGCUCUAGGUCCCCGGCUCGGGUGGGGUCACACGGUCCUGCCCUAGAGUCCCCAUCUGGCCCUGGAGCUGCAGAAGCAGCUUCUGAGGGGCUUCCCAGGCCUGCAUUUCACAGAUGGGGAGCUCAGCCCUCGAAGGCCGCAGAGACGCCUCCCAGGCCCGUCUGCCAGGGCGCCGGCCACAAUCCUGCAGGGCCAAGGACUGGACUCCAGGCAAGUCCCUGCGCUCCAGCUGGACGGCCCUGUUCCAGGGAGGAGGUGCUCGGUUGACACCAUCAGGGAGGGAGGGUGGGCACUGCUGGGCUGAGUUCACCCCCAGGGCUGGCCAGAUGGGGCCAGGAGGGACAGAGCAAGGGGGGUGAAGGCCGUGGUGGGAGGGUCCCAUGAUGAUGGGCCAGGGCUCGUGUAGAAAUGGGGGAAUUGGUUCCCCAUGGCCCAGGACAGCUGAGAGGAGGUGGAGGGGCCCCAGGGGAGUGUACGUCAGGCUUUGCGGGGCACGGGGGCCACUCAGCAGCGCUGGGGCAGGUGCCUCUGCUGUCAGCUCCACCCGACAGGCAGACGAAGGCCAGUGGGGCCAUCGCUUCCUGGGGCGACCCUGGCAGUGGUUGGGAGACGCCCAGAUGGAGGGGGAGGCUGACCAAGGGCCCCGCAGGGCGGGCUGCAACUUUUCUGUUGAUCCUGGAAUGUAGCUGGUGCAGUGAGAGGGAAAGAGAAUUGAAAAACUCAGGCUGCCAUAGGUUCUGCGAUGAGAGGUGCAGGAGGCAGGAGCCUGGCCCAGGGGGUGCUGGUGCCUCCCCGGGGUCUGGGCGGAGAGAACAGGAGGAAUGGCUGGGAAGUGGCUGAGGGAGCCAGGAGGCCGGGGGGCCGGGGGCUGCAGGGGAGGCUGUGGGGGUCCUGGCAGCCAGGAGGCCCCAGGUGGUUUUGAGGCUCGCUCUUGCGCGGUGCCUGAGAAGAGGGUGAAGGAGCUGGGGCAGGCCCCAUCCUGGGCAUUGGAGAUGAUGAAACCGAGCAGACCUGGCCCAUGUGGAGCUGGCAUGGGGGACACAGCCCAGAGACAGAGAAGCUUAUGAGGAAGUGAGGAGGUGGCGUCACAAGGGUGGGGAGGGGGCCUUGGGGAAGGGCGGCCUUGGAUCAGAGGCUCACCACAAGCCUGGCAUUUCAGCCAGGGCUGGAGAAGGCAGGGACGCCUGGGUGAGAGGCAAAGGGCACAGCCAUGCAAAGGCCCUGGGGCAGGACGGCACCUGGUAUGCGGGAGGAACAGAGUGAGGAGAGGAGGGCAGGGCGUGCAGGGCCUUGUGGGCCUCAGGGAGGACUUGGGCACCUACGCCGAGGGAGUGGAGCUCCUGGGUGCGUGUCCAGAUGGGAAAGGCAGGGUCGUAUCUGUGGGGACCUGACAAGGGCAGGGGAAGCGGAGACCAGGGUGCAGGCUCCGCCCCCACCCAAGGCCGGGCCCAGCCAGAGGAGGGGCAGGGCAGGGCAGGAGGUUUCUGGAUGUUUGUUGGGUUUGGUUUGGUUUUGUUUUGUUUUGUUUAUUGUGGUAAAAUACAAAAUCUACCGUCUUACAGUGA